CAAAAGAGAGAUCCCUGGACUCUGCAGAGUGAAGAGAAAAUAGCAAACGAUCCAGACGGCAGGGAGUGCAUCAAAGGUGUGAACACAGAUUCUUUCAGAUUUUUAGACUCAGCCUGCUGCCCAGCAGAAUAAUGAGAUAAUGGCAGAACAGUACGAACCAGACUCCACGUGAAGAUAGAAGAAUCAACUUUAAGACCUUUUUGAUGAGCCUCUUUUAAUCCUUUUCCUGCUGUGUCCCAAUUUUCCACAUCAAGAGUGCCUGCCUGUGGAAACCAUGGGCCAUGCAUCAUAAUCUCCUGCAGAAGCUUAAUGUCUGUGAAUUAACCUGAGUUCCAGGCUGUCUCAAUAGAACUUGAAACAACUGCACGUAGUGUUUUUUUCAACAGACAAGUUCUGCCCCACGUUACCCUGAUUCAGAAAACUUCCCGUUCGCAGUACUUUAGAGCACCGACCUCAUAUCGCUCCCAGUACCUCUUCAGGGCACUGACCUUAUAUCCGCUGCCAGCCGACUCAUCCAGGUUUCCCCAUUCACCUUGUGAAUUUCAGUUCCUCUACUCCAGCAGAACCUUCUUUGUUCACGUCCUCAAAGUCCUAUGUUCGGAGGCCACUUGUCCGACAUCCUCGGAGUCCCUCUUCUGGGUCACCAGUUGCCACCUGCACAGACCUUGGGGGACUGAACGAAGGGGGCGAACAUUGGAAUAAAAGACAAAGAUUCCCCACUGCUCCAAUGCAUCACCUCAGUUCCUUGUGUUUUCUGCACUGCCAGCAUGAUACACACAAUACCCUGAUACUCCUACCAAUGUCUGAGUCAGAGAGGAGCUCUAAAUUGGGAAGUAAUGCAGGAAACAAGCCUUGUAAAAAUCAACUUGGAUUCACUUUUCAGUUACAUCUGAGUGAUCUACAGCUAUUUCAAGCUGAAAGGAAAAUUUCUGGGUGUAAGCAUUUUGAAAAACCCGUCAGUGACAAUUCCUCAGUUUCACCGCUUGAAAAAAUUUCUUCCAGUGUCAAAUCCCACCUUUUAAAUAAAUAUAGAAAUAAUUUUGAUCAUGCUCCAUUACUUCCACAAGAACAGAAAGCACACAUUAGGGAAAAAGCUUAUAAAUGUAAUGAGCACGGCCAAGUCUUUAGAGCAUCUGCAAGCCUUACUAACCAAGUAAUCCAUAACGCAGAUAAUCCUUACAAAUGCAGUGAAUGUGGCAAGGUCUUUAGUUGCAGUUCAAAGCUUGUGAUACAUCGAAGAAUGCAUACUGGAGAGAAGCCUUACAAAUGUCAUGAAUGUGGCAAGCUCUUCAGUAGCAAUUCAAACCUUUCACAACAUCAAAGAAUUCAUACUGGAGAGAAGCCUUACAAAUGUCAUGAAUGUGACAAGGUCUUUCGAAGCAGUUCAAAGCUUGCACAACAUCAAAGAAUUCAUACUGGAGAGAAGCCUUACAAAUGUCAUGAAUGUGACAAGGUCUUCAAUCAAAUUGCACACCUUGUACGACAUCAAAAAAUUCAUACUGGAGAGAAACCUUACAGUUGUAAUAAAUGUGGCAAGGUCUUUAGUCGCCAUUCAUAUCUAGCAGAACAUCAAACGGUUCAUACUGGUGAGAAACCUUACAAAUGUGAAGAAUGUGGCAAAGCAUUUUCAGUGCGUUCCAGCCUCAUAACCCAUCAGUUAAUUCACACUGGAAGGAAACCUUACAAAUGUAAAGAAUGUGACAAGGUCUUUGGGCGCAAGUGUUUCCUGACCUCUCAUCAGAGAAUUCAUACUAGAGAGAGACCUUAUGGAUGCAGUCAGUGUGGCAAGAUCUUUAGUCAGAAAUCAGACCUUAUACGACAUCGAAAAACUCAUACUGAUGAGAAGCCUUACAAAUGUAAUAAAUGUGGCACAGCGUUUAGAGAGUUUUCAGACCUUACUGCCCAUUUUCUAAUCCAUAGUGGAGAGAAACCUUAUGAAUGUAAAGAAUGUGGCAAAGUCUUCAGGUACAAGUCUUCUCUAACCAGUCAUCAUAGAAUUCAUACUGGAGAGAAGCCUUACAAAUGUAACAGAUGUGGCAAGGUCUUCAGUCGCAGUUCAAACCUGGUAUGCCAUCAGAAAAUUCAUACAGGAGAAAAGCCUUACAAAUGUAAUCAAUGUGGCAAGGUCUUUAAUCAAGCAUCAUACCUUACAAGACAUCAAAUAAUUCAUACUGGAGAGAGGCCUUACAGAUGUAGUAAAUGUGGCAAAGCAUUUCGAGGGUGUUCAGGCCUUACUGCCCAUCUUGCAAUCCAUACUGAAAAGAAAUCUCAUGAGUGUAAAGAAUGUGGCAAGAUCUUCACUCAGAAGUCUUCCCUCACCAAUCACCAUAGAAUUCACAUUGGAGAGAAACCUUACAAAUGCACCCUGUGCAGUAAGGUCUUCAGUCACAAUUCUGACCUUGCACAGCAUCAGAGAGUUCAUUCAUGAGAGUCCCUACAAACUGUAUGGCAAAACCAUCAUCAUGAGUUCUAGCAUUAAUCAACAUCAGUGAGUCCAUACUAAGUGGAAAUCAUAUAAAUGAAAUGUAUGUGACACAGGCUUUAUCAAGGCCUGCCAAAUCACUGGACAUCACCACAUCACUGUGGAGGAUGAAAGCACACAGAUGAAUUGUGUGUACUUGGGCUAUUAUUCAAGGACCAUUGCUAUAGAACACGAUAGGAUUUACACAAGAAGUAACUCUGUCUCUGGUUCUCUGAUACUAAUCUAUGAUAUUGCAUGAUGCAGAAUAAUGCUAAGUCAAAAUAUGUUGAAUCUCAUGACCUGAUGUAUAUCAAAGGUGCAACGGCUUGUAAAUGACCAGUUUUAUUCAGGCUAUAAAGCAUUCAAUUAUUUGGGGCUUAUAGAAAAGGCUACUUUACUCUUUGUGACUUCGAAAUCUUUUCAUGUGCCUUCCAUACAGGCCAUUCACUGUGGUCCCUGGGAAAGAAUCAGUAGGAUGACAGGGCUGACUUCAUUAGCUGAGGAUUAUUUCUAUCCAAUUUCCUGAUGAAGGACAUUGCCUUUUGAGAUUAAAUAUUGUCUGAUUUAGAGAGCAUGGAGGUGGGCAGAGUAACAUAAAACUGAUGACCGUCAUCAUACUGUUGCAGUUAGCACACUUUCUCCUGACAUAAGUGCACAGAGCUUCAGUGUCCACCAACUGACCAUGAAAUAGAGUAUGCUGUAAUCUUAAGGCAUAGGUUAUUAGUGGGAAGAGAGUAAUAGGUUGCUAGUGUCUGAUUAUAUGGUAGAAAUAAUGCAAGGAAAAAGGUAGCCACCUUCUCCAUUGAACAGCAGUACCUGCUGUUUAGCAAAGACUGAUGAGAAGUAGACUUUUUUUUUUUUGGAGAUAGAGUCUCACUCUGUUGCCCAGGCUGGAGUGUAGUGGUGUGUUCUUGGCUCACUGCACCCUCCGCCUCCUGGGCUCAAGCAGUCCUUCUGCCUUAGCCUCCUAAGUAGCUGAGACUACAGACGUGCGCCACCACACCCAGUUCAUUUUUGUAUUUUUAGUAGAGACAGUGUUUACCAUGUUGGCCAGGCAGGUCUCCAACUCCUGACCUCAAGUGAUAUGUUCACCUCAGCCUCCCAAAGUGCUGGGAUUACAGGCAUGAACCAUGGUGCCCAGCCUCAUUUUUGAAAUGGAAUAGAGAACAGUUAUAUCACAGUUGAGAGUUUAAUCAAAAUGACCGGAUCAGCAUAUUCUUUUUUUAGAUGAGACAGAGUUUCGCCCUUGUCACCCAGGCUGUAGUGCGGUGGCGCGAUCUCGGCUCACUGCAACCUCCGCCUCCCGGGUUCAAGCAAUUCUCCUGCCUCAGCCUCCCAAGUAGCUGGGAUUACAGGCGUGUACCACCAUACCCAGCUAAUUUUUGUAUUUUUAGUAGAGAUGGGGUUUCACCACGUUGGCCACACUGGUCUCAAACUCCUGACCUCAGGCGAUCCAUCUGCCUCAGCCUGAAAGUGCUAGGAUUACAGGCGUGAGCCACCACACCUGGCCAGCUCAGCAUAUUCUUAAGUAGGAUUCACAUUUAAUUCUUGGUAUUAUAAGUUGCAACCAUUUGAUUUAGAAUGUAUGCAGCUCUCAUGUUUGUAGUAAUAAAGUUUCAUUUUUCCUAA